GUUUCCCAUUGCUGGGGAGACCUCAGGAAACUUAAAAUCAUGGUGGAAGGCACCUUUUCACAGGGUGGCAGGAGAUAGAAUGAGUGCAGGCGGGGGAAAUGGCAGACAUUUGUAAAAUCAUCAGAUCUUGUGAGACUCAUUCACUAUCAUGAGAACAGCAUGGGGGAAACAGCCCCCGUAAUCCAAUUACCUCUUCCUGGUUCUGCCCUUGACACGUGGGGAUUGUGGGGACUAUGGGGAUUACAAUUCAAGCUGAGAUUUUGGGUGGGGACACAGCCAAACCAUAUCAAUGGAUGACUUCCUGAAAGAAUUGCUGGGUCUGUGAGUAUACAUACUGUAAAAUAUGUGCAAGAGAGACAGUAGAACAUAGCUGCUAAGUACAGAGCCUUGGAGUCAUUGGCUUGAGUUUGAAGCCUGGCCUCACCAUUUCCUAGCUCUGUAACCUUAGGCAAGUUACUUAACCUCUUUGUGCCUUCAUUUCCUCAUCUGUAAAGUGGGGAAUAGCAGAAGUACCUGUGUCAUGACAUAGAGCUUGGACUUGUGCCUAGCUCAUAGUAAGAGAUUAUUAUACAUGUCUCAAGAUUACUGUUCAGAAAGCUGCAUAUCCAUGCGUAUAUCUUGUCACCAAAGGAGCCUAGCGUCUAGCAGAGGCAUGUCAGAAUGAAAGGACCAACAGUGGAUGAGAUGGCCUUCCACUGCUCAUUUUUGCCAUCAGCACUGAUUAUUAUUGCACGUUUUAGUAUCAUUCUAGUCAGCCAAAAAAUGAUGUCAGGGUAUAUUAAUUUGCAUUUUUAAUUAGUAAGAUUGUGUAUUUUCAAAUACAUUUUGUGAGCAUUCGUUGAUGUUUUUUCCUACUGUGAAAUACUUGUUUGUAUCUUUUGCCAGUAUUUAUAUUGGGAUAUUCAUCUUUUUCUUUUUUCUUUUUUUUUUUGAGAUGGAGUUUCGUUCUUAUUGCCCAGGUUGGAGUGUGGUGGCAUAAUCUUGGCUCACUGCAACCUCCGCCUCCCGGGUUCAAGCGAUUCUCCUGCCUCACCCUCUUGAGUAACUGGGAUUAUGGCAUCCACCACCAUGCCCAGGUAAUUUUUUAUAUUUUUAUUAGAGAUGGGGUUUCUCCAUGUUGGCCGAGCUGGUCUCAAACUCCUGACCUCAGGUGAUCUGCCCGCCUCGGCCUCCCAAAGUGCUGGGAUUACAGGCGUGAGCCACUGUGCCCGGCCAAUCUUUUUCUUAUUGAUUUAUGAAAAUUCUGUAUAUUUUAAGGAGACAACCUCUUGAAAAAUUACUCAAAUAUUUUCCCAGGGUUCUUUUAUUUUGUUUAUGUCUCUUGACUUUGUUGUGUGUUAAUUUUUUUAAUUGACAAAUAAAAAUUGUAUAUAUUUAUGGUGUACAACAUGAUGUUUUGAUACAUGUAUGCAUUGUAGAAAGGAUAAAUUAAACUAAGUAACAUCUCUAUUACCUUACACAUUUAUUUUUUAUGGUUGGAACACUUAAAAUCUCUCGGCAGUUUUCAAGUGUACGAUAUAAACUAUAGUGACAAUAUUGUACAAUAAAGCUCUUGAACUUAUUCCUCCUGUCUGACUGAAAUUUUAUAUCCUUUGACCACCAUUUUUUCAGUCAUCCCACUGCACAGCCUCUGGUAACCACUGUUCCACUUUCUGCUUCUGUGAGUUCAACUUUUUUAGAUUCCACAUGUAAGUGAGACCAUGUGGUAUUUGUCUUUUUGUGCCUGUCUUCUUUUAACUAGCAUAAUGUUUAUAAGAUUCGUCCAUGUUGUCACAAAUGAUAGGAUUUCUUUUUUUUAAGGCUUAUUAGCAGUCCAUUGUAUAAAUAUACCAUUUUUUUUUUAUUCAUUCAUCUGUUGAUGCACACUUAGGCUGCUUCCAUGUCUUGGCUGUUGUGGAUAAUGCUGCAGUGAACAUGGGGGUGCAGUAUCUCUGACAUACUGAUUUCAUUUCCUUUGGAUAUAUGCCCAGAAGUAGAAUUGCUGGAUCAUAUGGGAGUUCUAUUUUUAAUAUUUUUUCAUACUCUUUUCCAUAAUGGCUAUACCAAUUUGCAUUUUCACUAACAGUGUACAAGGGUUCUCUUUUUUUUUCCCCACAACCUAAACAACACUUGCUGUCUUUCAUCCUUUUUGAUGUAGCUUUUUUUUUAACAGGCAUGAGAUAUUAUCUCCUAGUGGUUUUAAUUUGCACUUUCCUGAUGAUUAGUGAUGUUGAACACUUUUUUUCAUCUACCUGUUGGCCAUUUGUGACUUGGUUGUGAUUUUUACUGUUGAGGAAUUGUCAACAUUGUUUUAGUCAGUUCUGACUUUUUCUUCAUGGCUCUGGUGGAUUGUGUCAUAUUGUCAUACAUAAGGAGAAAAGAAUUUAUGAAUGUGAUGAACAUAAUGGAAUGUGGCUCCCUUCCUUCCAUUCUCAUCUCCGCUCUGUUAAUUGACCUCUGGGUUCAAUGAGUGGCUAAUGUAACUGAAGUCCCUGGCUCUCUACUGGAAGUGAAUGUAAAAGAAACUGGCACUGGACUUUCUUUCCCAUGAACAUUUUAGAGACCAAGCCACAGAGUGAAGACCAGGAAAUUGUGGAUCUUUGGAUAAGCUUAGUCUCAAUAUUUUUUUAUUUUUAGAAACAGUACAAGACCCUUUCUCAAAUAAAUAAAUAAAACUUAUAUGGGUAAACAAAAGGCCAAGAACAGUGAAGGCAAUCUUGAAGAACAAAGUUAGAGGAGUUAGGAUUUAGCCUAUAGAAUACUCAGCAGACUUUUUCAAUAAAAGACAAGAUAUCAAAUAUUUUAGACUUUGCAGGCUACGUGGCUUGCAGGCUAUAAUUUGCUGAACCCUGCUCUAUAGGGUGUCCAAAUUUCUUGUUAAGUUGUAUAAUUAAAAAGGGGUGUGCAAGGAUGGGUAAAUAGACCAAUAGUACAGAAAGUCCAGAAACAGACCCACACAUCUAUGUCUUACCAAUAAAUGGUGCAAGUCAAUUAGAUAUUCAUAUGGGAAAAAAAUAAAUGGAUACUACUUGGGCGUGGUGGUGCAUGUCUGUAGUCCCAGCUACUUGGGAGGCUGAGGUGAGGAUUGCUUGAGCCCAAGAGUUUGAGGCCAUAGUGAGCUAUGAUUGAGCCACUGCGCUCCAGCCUGGGCAACAGAGCAAGACCCUGUCUCCUGAAACAAAACAGAACAAAAAACCCAAUCUUGUAUCAUACACUAAAAUAAAUUCCAAGUAGAAUUUUAGAUCCAAAUGUUGAAGAUAAAAAAUAAUAAUAAAGAUUUAAGAAGCUAACAUGCCUACCUUGGGAGCAGGAACAAAUAUCUCAAAUAAGAACAAGAAAUGGUCAUCAUCAAGGAAAAGUUUAUAAAUUGGACUACUUUAAUAUUAGAGACUCUAUUAAAAGUUAUCAGUAAGAAGAGUGAAAAGCAAGAAGACACAAAGUGGGACAAGGUAUUUCCUCCCCUCCCCUCCCCUCCCCUCUUCUCCUCUCUUCUCUUUUCUUUUCUUUCUUUUUUUUUGACAGAGUCUCCCUUUGUCGCCCAGGCUGGAGUGCAGUGGUGCAAUCUUGGCUCCCUGGAACCUCUGCCUUCCAGGUUCAAGUGAUUCUCCCGCCUCAGCCUCCCGAGUAACUGGAACUACAGGCACAAGCCACCACACCCGAUUAAUUUUUUAUAUGUUUAGUAGAGGCGGAGUUUCACCAUGUUGACUGAGCUGGUUUUGAACUCCUGAGCUCAAAUGAUCCGCCUGCCUCCCAAAGUGCUGGGAUUACAGGCGUGAGCCACUGCGCUGGGCCAGGACAAGAUAUUUCACAAAUAUAACUAAUAAAGCGUUCAUAUCUAGAAUCUUUAAGGAGUUUCUAUAAAUCAGUAAGGCUAAGAUAGACAACCAAAUAGAAAAUAUGCUCUCAAAAGAUAUCUAAUUGACCAGUAAGAUGCUUAACAUCAUUAGUCAUCAGGAAAAUGAAAAUUAAAACCUCAGUAGGAUACUAUUACUGUACACCUGCCAGCAUGGCUAAAAUUCAAAAUCUGAUGAUAUGCAAGGUUGACAAAGAUAUGGAGCAACAGGAGUGCUCUUACAUGCUGGUGGAAAUAGGAAUUAGUGUGAUAACCACUUAGGAAAAUUCUUUGGCAGUUAUUUCAGUUAUCUAUCGCUGUAUCCAGGCCACUCUCAAAGUUGGGGAAAUAAUUGGCAUCCUGUUUUCAGAUAAUAUUUAGAGCAGGGAAAAUGAAACUAUUAUUUGAAUGGAGAAAUUUAGGAAAAUUUUCACAUUAACAAAAGAAAAAAGUUGGAAAGAAUGGCAGUUUGACUAGCCCAACACAAAUAGAGGGAAGAAGAGGAAACAUUAUACAAUAAUAAAAGUAAGGGGAAGGAAUAAGAUCAUUGUAUCAAUUAUUAGGCUAAAUGUGAGCAGACUGAAUUUUGCCAUUAAAAAGGGCAUGUCAGGUUGCACGGGUGGCUCACACCCGUAAUCCCAGCUCUAUGGGAGGCCAAGGCAGGAGGGUAUCUUGAGCCCAGGAGUUCGAGACUAGCCUGGGCAACAUGGGGAAACCCCAUCUCUACAAAAAAUAAAAAAUAAAAAUAAAUAAAAAUAGCCAGGAGUGAUAGCAUGCAUCUGUAGUCCCAGCUACUCUGGAGGCUGAGGUGGAUUGCUUGAGGAUUGCUUGAGUCCAGGAGGUCGAGGCUGCAGUGAGCCUUGGUUGUGCCGCUGUACUCCAGCUUGGGUGACAAAGCAAGACCCUGUCUCAAAAAAAAGAAAGAAAGAAAAAAAAGAUGUGUCAGACUGAACUAAAUAAACCUCUGGAGAAUAAUGUUUAUAAGCACUUCUCAAAGCAAAAUGAGUAGGUGAAAAUAAAGCAGAAAUGAAAGAGCAGGAAAAUAGUGAAAAACAAAAACAAAUUUCCUCAAAGCAGAACAGCAUUAGACAAAGUGGAUUUCAGGUUAGAGGCACUAAAUGAGGUAAAGACAGACAUUAUAUACUGAUAAGGGGCACAAUUUAUGAUCAUGUAUGAACCAAAUAGCAUCAAGUAUCAUAUCAGGCAAAAACAUAAAACAAAAACUAUUAGUAAUAUAAGGUGAACUUGGUAAAAGUUCAGCUAUUGUGAGGCAUUUCAGUAUAUCCUUAAGAGUAUUGAAUCUAGAGGAACUGAAUAAUCAGUAAUGAUAACAGUACUAUAUUAAUAUAUUAUCUGAGAUUUAUUGGGUGCUUACUGUGUGCCAGGCACUCUUCUAAGUGUUUUACAGUAUUAAAUCAUUGAUCCUCACAAAAAACUUAUGAUACUCAACAAAAAGGCAUUUUUCCAGUGAAGAUAUGCAAAUGGUCAAUAAGCACCUAAAAAGAUGUUCAGCAGCAUCAGUCAUAGGGAAAUGCAAAUCAAAACCACAAUGAAGUACCACUUCACACCCACUGGGGUGGCUGUAAUAAAAAGAUGGACAAUAACAAGUGUUGACAAGGAUGUAGAGAAAUUGGAACUCUCAUACAUCACUAGUAGAAGUUUAAAAUUAUGCAACUGCUUUGGAAAACAGUCUAGCAUUUCCUGAAAUGGUUAAACAUAGAGUUACCAUAUGACACAGCAGUUCAGCUCCUAGGUUUAUACCUGAGACUAUUGGAAACAUUUGUCCACAUAAAAACUUGUGUGUGAAUUCUCAUAGUAGCAUUAUUGAUAACAGAAGGUAGAAACAACCCAGAUGUCUAUCAGCUGAUGAAGGGAUUAAUGAAAUGUGGUUUCUCCACACAAUGGAAUAUUAUUUGGACAUAAAAAGGAUACAUGCUACCAUAUGGGUUAACCUUGAAAACAUUAUGCUAAGUGAAAGAAUCAAGUUAUAAAAGACUACAUAUUUCAUUUUCAUGAAAUGGGUAGCAUAGACCAGUCUGUAGAGACUCAGUGUAGAUGAGUGGUUGUUAUGAUUUAGAGUGGGGUUGGGAGGGGGUAAUUAGGUAUAAAUGCUAAUGGGCAGGAGGUUUCUUUUUAGGGUCAUGAAGAUGUUCUAAAAUUGAUUGUGAUUCUAAAGUCAGAUUUGCACAGCCUAUGAAUUUAUAAAAAACCAUUGAAUUGUACUUAAAAGUAUAUAUAUAUAUUUUUUUUGCGGGGGUGGGGGUUGGGUGCAUGGAGUCUCCCUCUGUCACCGAGGCUGGAGUGCAGUGGCACGAUCUUGGCUCACUGUAACCUCUGCGUCCAGGGUUCAAGUGAUUCUCCUGCCUCAACCUCCUGAGUAGCUGGGAUUACAAGCAUGCCCCACCAUGCCUGGCUAAUUUUUUCUAUUUUUUGAGUGACGGGGUUUCACCAUGUUGGCCAGGUUGGUCUUGAACUCCUGACCUCAAAUGAUUCACCUGCCUCAGCUUCCCAAAGUACUAGGAUUACAGGCCUGAGCCACCGUGCUGGGCUGUAAAUACAUAUAUUUAUGAUAUGUGAAAUAUGUUUUAAUGAAGUUGUUAUUGAAAACAAAUUACGAUUAUGUUAAUUGACUUUAAAGGAGUUCUCCAAGGUACAUUUCAAUAAGGAAAGCAAUAUGCAUUAUUUUGUAAAAUAGUGACAUAUGAGCAUGGAAUAAAUAUGGAAGGAUAUAUGAUAGGUUGCCAGUUUGGGUUAUCAAGAUAGGAGGGUGCUGAUAUGGGGAAAGAGGGAUUCGAGGGGAAGGAGGUAGCAAUGAAAUUUAGGAAAAGAAAACAACCUGUAUUUAAAUAGAAAGCCAUGAUGUGUCGUAUCUCUAAUUUACUUUCAAAUGAUUCAACAAGACAGCAUGUAUGCAUACAUAAUUACAUAUAUACACAUAUGUAUGCACACAUAUAGAUGGAUAGAUAAAGCAAAGAUGGCCAAAUGUAACAAUUGUUGACUCUAUGUGGGGGUUAUAUGGAUAGUUAUUUUACUAGUCUGUCAAAUUUUAUCUGUGUUUGAUAGUAAUAAAAAAUCGGGGGUAAAAACUCCACCAGAAUGUUUUCUGUGAUCACAUUAUUGUAAUAUUUAAAAUAUUUACAUAUUUAAAAAUUUUAGUAACACUUAAUAAGCAGAAAAAUGCCUUAAACAUUUCAAAAUCAUGAAAUUAUUUUUCUAGUCCUUUUGCUUUUGUUUAAGUUAAAUUUCUAGGCUGUUUGGAAUUUCUUUUUCUUUCCUUUUUGUUUUUUUUUUUGAGACGGGGUGUCAUUCUGUCACCCAGGCUGGAAGUGCAGUGGCACAAUUAUGGCUCACUGUAGCCUCGACUUCCCGGGAUUAGGUGAUUCUCCCAUCUCAGCCUCCUGAGUAGCUAGGGCUACAGGUUGCCACCACACCUGGAUAAUUUUUUUUUAUUUUUUAUUUUUUGUAGAGACAGAGUUAAUUGUGUUGCCUGGGCUGGUCUUGAACUCCUGGCUCAAGCGGUUGGCCCACCCCCACCUCCUAACAUACUGGGAUUACAGGGGUGAGUCACCGAGCCUGGCCUGGAGUUUCAUAAUCUAUGUUUAUUAAUUUUGAUGUGGUUUCUUUUUGAUCCAUUACUUUUUUUCUAGGUAAACAGUGGUAUCAUCUGGAGGUAAUGCUGGUUUUAUGAUUCCUUUCCAAUAUUUUUGGCUUAUUGCAUAGGUUAGAAUAUCUGGAACAAUUUUGAAUGAUGAUGGGAGUAAGCGUCCUUGUUUUAAAUUUUUAAUGGCAGUCUUGUUUCAGUUUCAAAGUUUUAUGUUUUUUGAUAAAUAUUAUUGAUUGGGUUAAGGACAUUUUCAUCUAACAUUAAAAUAGUUGAGUGAAACAGAGUAUCCAAAUCAGAAAAUUAAAUGAAAAAAAAAAAAAAUUAAGAAAAGCAAUCCUAAAAUGUAGAGCAAAAAUAAUACCCAAAGGUAGAGGGUGAUAAUCAGCCCACAGGACUGAUAGAAGUUCUUACAUUCAGGCAAAAACCCUGUUAGUCCUAGAUGUAUACCAAAUCAGUAUGUUAGAAUAAAACAACAAAGACUGGGUAUGGCAGCUCACGCCUGUAAUCCCAGCACUUUGGGAGGCUGAGGUGGGCAGAUCACCAGAGGUCAGGAGUUCGAGACCAGCCCGUCCAACAUGGUGAAACCCUGUCUCUACUGAAAAUACAAGAAAAAAUAGUUGGGCAUGGUGGUGGGUGCCUGUAAUCCCAGCUACUCGGGAGGCUGAGGAUUCAAUUGCUUGAACCCGGGAGGCAGAGGUUGCAGUGAACCGAAAUUGCACCAAUGCAUUCCAUCCUUGGUGACAGAGUGAGCCUCCGUCUCAAAAAAAAAAGAAUAAAACAACAAAAACAGAUGUUACAGAGCCUGUGAGAUCUGAGAAAUACUGGGACAUCACUGGCAUGUGCCCAAAAGAGUUUCACUGAAUAAAUCUUGGGGCCGAUGUGUGUUGGAGAUAAGAGCUCUUCUACAAGGAAGUAUGCCUAUUUGCCAAAAAUAAGCAAAUAUAUUUUUCUUAGCACUGCUUUAAGGAACGUUCGUUUUGUUAAAGGUUAAAAUUACUAGAUGGGUUAGUUGCCUUGCAAGUAUACUUUUGUGGAAUGAAUAUGAGUGUACUCUUAAUAAAUCUAUUGAUAUUUGUCAUAUUUUAAACUGAGUUCAUAUUUCCCAAUAUGGUCAAGAGUACAGACCAUGAAUAUGAAAAUAUGCUGAUGAAAAUAUGAAUAUGUUCUUAAUGAUAUAUUGAUCUUUAUUAAAUUUUAAACCAGGUUUAAAAUGUCCCAAUAUGGUCAAGAACAUAGCUCAUGAAUAUGAAUAUAAACUUAUGGAAAUGUUCAUGAAUAUAUUCAUGUUCAUUAAUUUUAAACUGUAUUAAAAAGUUUUCCCAAUAGGGUAAAGAAGAAUAUAUUCAUGAAUAUAUUCAUAAAGAGGAUAUAUUCAUGAAUAUAAUCAUUAUAAAGAAAAUAUUCACAUUUAUUGAAUAUUUUCACAAAGAAUAUAUUCAUAUGAAGACUAAACUACUCUACAACUCUUUGCAUUUUACAAAUUAGUUUUUAAAAUCCUGCUAUGAAGCAGAGUGUAAAUCAUUCUACUAAAAUUUCACUGAAAUCUUCGAAAAGUGAAAAAGUAUAAAUUUGGUAUCUUCAGUGAAUUGAUCUAUUUAUGAAUUGGCUCCUAGUGAAUAGUUCUUGGCAAAUUAAUUUAGAGCCCUCUCUCUCUGCAUGAGAUGAACCAUUAUUUAUUACUGCAUCUGCCCUGGGAAAACCAAGACAAAAAGAGGGGGAUAUUGAAAACAGCUGGGCUGAGUGUUCAGAACAGACUGAUUAAUAACACUAAAGAAAUAAAGGUUCUUGUUAGAAGGAAGGCCUGCAAGCCACUGCAUGAGAUUUAAGGACCACAGGUGCUCAGGCUGGUGAGACUGGUAUGGCAGGCAGUAUUUUGGGGCUGAAGAGUUUAGUGUAGUUACCAUGUGCAAAAUGAUACAAGUUUAAGUUUACUCAUAAUAGAAACUGGAAAAUUACAUGGCUUGCUUCGGGAGUUCCUCACUUCAUUUUGUUUUGGUAUUUCAGAAAAGAAAUUCUGAGGCUUUAGACAGUUUGCUACUCACAGAUCUCAUAAAUCAAGCAUUCUUCAUGACCUGGAUCUAUCUUGAGCAGAUCAAAGCUCUGAGCAGCUUGAAUAGUGCUCACCCAGAGGCUUACUGCCAGUAACAACCCAAAUUUCUUAGCCUAUUUGUUUUUGUUGUUGUUGUUUGUUUGUUUGUUUGUUUGUUUUAAAGCAGCAGUAAAACACAUUGUGGGUGCACAUUUUUUGGAAAAACCAGAAGUUCAAAUAUUAGUAAAAUAUUUGGACUUAACAUUUUAUGGGCACUCAGAAGUAACCAUCAACUUCACAUGUAUCUCUGAGCAAAAUAUUAACCACUAAUAACCAUUAGUAAAUGGAUGCUGAGUGGGCCAGAUCUUGCUGACACCUUGGUUAUAUGGUGUUUUGUGUGGGAUAUUAGUUUUCUGAGGUUUGUACAAAGGAAUUUGUAAAAUGCUUAAUUUUAUCAUUAACUUUACCACUUUACCAUUGAGCUUCUGAGCUUCUUUUUUUUUUUUUUUUUUUUUUGAGACCCAGUUUUGCUCUUGUUGCCCAGGCUAGAGUGCAGUGGCAUGAUCUCGGCUCACCUCAACCUCCACCUCCCAGGUUCAAGUGAUUCUCCUGCCUCAGCCUUCCUGAGUAGCUGGGAUUACAGGCAUGCGCCACCAUGCCUGUCUAAUUUUGUAUUUUUAGUAGAGAUAGGGUUUCUCCGUGUUGGUCAGGCUGGUCUCGAACUUCCGACCUCAGAUGAUCCACCCGCCUCGGCCUCCCACAGUUCUGAGCUUCUUAAAGUCAAUACCCAUGUCCAAUUUAUAUUUGCUGUGCUAUUGCAUCUAGCACAAUUUAUUGUGUGUAGAAGAUGCCUAAAGUUUGUUUUUAAUGAAUACAUAUAUGAAAUGUCUGUCAUGGAACUAUCUAUUUUCCUUUUAUUUGUAUUGCUAUUUUGCCCAUUAACUAAAGGAUAUGGAUGGUAAGCCUUGUCUAUGUCUCUAUUGUCUUAGUAAAGAUGCCCUUUUUUCUUGUAUAUCCAACCUUUGUGCACUAAAAUCCUCUUUCCCCACAGCUUCACAGAAUACUAGAUUCAUUGUUUAGCCCUUUUCUUAUCUGUAGCCUUCUUUACUGUAAAGUGGAGGGAAAAUGUUUAGUGAUUUGAAAAGUUUCAAAAUUUUUCUGUACUAUUAGACUUGAAUGAAUGUCAGAUCUGAGAGGGCCCUGCGAGACCACUAUUCAAUCCUUUUGUUUUACUCAUGAAAAACUCAGAGUUCUAAUUGCUUUCGCACUAUAACUCAUGCCAUGCUAUUUUGUAAUUGCUUAGUUGUUGGCAUUUCUAGCUAGACUUUAAAUUCAGUGGGAAUAGGGACCACAUCUAUCUUAUUUAAUGCUGUAUUUCUGACACAGCACAGUGCUUAGAAGAGAAUAGGUGUUCAGUUAAUGGUUCAGUUAUGAAUAAAUAAAUAAAUAAAUAAGUCAGGAUUGGUGAAGGGACUUGCUCAAAGUCAUGUGACUAUUUAGGGGGCAGCCCCCAGUUGCUGAAUCUGUUAAGCACAUUAAAAGUCAGAGCUCUGUAAUCUACUCUGCCAUCCUGGAGAGAGUCAAGGUCAGUGGAAAUGACUAAUUUUUCUUAAGUGUGUUUGUUAAGCUCUGCAACUUAUACAUUUCCACAUGUUGGCUUUCAGUAUACCGGAGACUGCUAUAUAGGAAAGCAGCUGACCAAGGAAAUGUAGAGGAUGUGCUGCCAUUAUUUUUGCCUUGGAGGCUUUUUCAAGAGACACUUCUACUUUUCAAAGCAGUGAAACUUCAUCUUAGGAAAAGAAAUUUUCCCCAGCUACAAUCUAAUUUUUAAUCUUUUUUUUUUAAUUUUAACUUUCCACACUAUACCAUCAUAUUAAUCUUAUUUUUAAAUGUAUUGUUUCUGAAAUCCUGAGUGCCCCAGCGAUCAAAAACUCUGCUUAGGAUUCAGUUCAUUAAUGUGAGGGCUCAGACUCUUAAGGUACUUAUAAAACCUCAAGGACUAUUGAUACUGGUCAUUUGUGAAUUCAAACAGAAACUUCCAGAAUCAUCAUGACCUUUUAAAGUUUCAUCCUUAGUUUUUCUGGUCUACCGUUGACCUCCAUUAAUGAUCCCAAAUCUGCUUGUUUUGCAGAAAAUAAAAUGUGUACGUGGUCACAGAAACGGUUGUUACCUGAUGAUCUUUAAGAUCUUGGAGUAUAAUACUGUGGGUCAUUGAUGUCUUUUACUGUUAAGUUCCCCAUCAGUACCUAUAUUCACCUUUUGACUGCAUGGUAAAUUGCUUUGCUUAUGUAUGAACUUAGGUACUUGUAAUGAAGUCAGAAUUUAAACCAUAUUGAGGGAGAAUGGGAAAAAGAAUAAGACUGGAAAGGAAGAAACUGUCAAGUCAGGGUUUGGCUUUUCUUGUUAUAUGCCAUUCUAUUAAAAUAUGUAUAUUUUUGUACUUUUUUUGAACAUAUGAAAUGAUCAUAUUUUACUUGACAUUUAUCACUUAUUUAGCAGCAGAAAAAUACAUGUAAAUGGAAAUGCUAUCAUCCCUUUGAAACAUGUCUUUUUAACACUUAGGAUUCGUGCUAUUUGCCAGGAGGGAGUUUUUCUACUUACAGAGCAUCUGGGAGAUGAAUUGGAAAGGCAGACUUCUGGUCUGGAGUGACACUGCUGAUCCUGUAACAUGGAGGAUUGUCUUCAUACCUCAUCUGAGAAUCUGUCCAAAUUGGUCAGCUGGGCCCAUAGCCAUGGGACUAUUUGCAGCCUCAUUCCAAACCUGAAACACUUGCUUUCUGAAGGUUCCCAUGGGAACCUGACAGCAAUGUGGGGCUGUAGUGCUGGCCAUGCUUAUCACUGGCCACUAACAGCUACUUGCAGAGCUGGGUCCCAAGAGAGGGUCUGUUUCCAGGAUAACAGAAGUUUUAACUCUGAUAGUCCCAGUAUAAUCGGGGUGCCCUCUGAGACACAGACUAGCCCUGUUGAAAGGUACCCUGGGAGACCAGUGAAAGCAAAGCUAGACUGUAACCGGACCAGAGACUCUUGUGACUUCUCCUACUGUAGUGAGCCCUCUGAACUGGAUGAAACUGUUGAAGAAUAUGAAGAUGAGAACACCCUGUUUGACAUGGUUUGUGAGUCUUCUGUUACAGAUGAGGAUAGUGACUUUGAACCCCAAACCCAAAGGCCUCAAAGCAUUGCUCGCAAAAGACCUGGGGUAGUCCCAUCUUCCCUCCAUUCAAGCUCCCAGACGCAGAUGGUUGACGAAUGCAGCAAUGAUGUCAUCAUCAAGAAAAUCAAACAAGAAAUCCCCGAAGAUUAUUACAUUGUGGCAAAUGCAGAACUGACAGGAGGAGUAGAUGGACCAGCCCUGUCCUUGACACAGAUGGCAAAACCCAAGCCUCAGACUCACGCUGGUCCCUCCUGUGUAGGGUCUGCUAAACUGAUUCCCCAUGUCACAUCUGCCAUCAGCACGGAGCUAGACCCACACGGUAUGUCUGCAUCCCCCUCUGUGAUCUCCAGACCAAUUGUCCAGAAGACUGCUAGGGUAUCUCUGGCUUCACCAAACAGAGGACCCCCUGGUACACAUGGCACCAACCAACAGGUGGCCAUGCAAAUGCCUGUGAGCACAUCCCAUCCUAACAAACAGAUCAGUAUCCCCUUGUCUGCCCUGCAGCUGCCUGGACAGGAUGAGCAAGUUGCCUCUGAAGAGUUCCUGUCCCAUCUGCCCAGCCAGGUCUCCUCCUGUGAGGUAGCCCUUUCUCCCUCAGUUAACACAGAGCCAGAAGUGAGCUCCAGUCAGCAGCAGCCCCCAGUCGCUCCAGCCAUAACCACUGAGGCCACAGCACAGUGCAUACCAGACCAGGAUGAAAGAGCAGCUGAGCUCAGCAGGGAGCAGAACGAGAAAACCAUCCGGAGCACGCAGACCGCGCUCCGCAAUUUCCGUGAGUUCCUCAUCUCCAAGUAUCCUUCUGAAACAAGAGAGAUUUAUGUCAUCCCUUGCAAGGAGUUGGAUGCCUACCUUGCCUCUUUCUUUGUUGAUGCCAGGCAGAAGGAUGGGUCCGAAUACGAACCCAACAGCUUGGCCAAUUACCAGUGUGGGCUCGAAAGGUACCUGAAAGAACACAGGUAUGGCUAUAGCAUCACCAGGGAUAAGGAAUUCAAGCGUUCCCAAGAGGCCCUGAAGCAGAAGCAAAUUGAACUCCGCUGUAAAGGAAAAGGAAAUAAGCCACACAAGUCCAUGAAGCUCACCUUUGCUGACGAGCUCAUCCUGCGGAAAAGGGGACUGCUAAGCCGAUAUAACCCCGAGGGUUUGCUCAACCUAGUCUGGCUCAACAACACAAAAGCUUUUGGGCAUUGCACAGGCUUCCAUGGAUCUACCUUAAAAUGGGGUGAUAUCCGGCUCCGGGUAACAGAGACGGGUCUCGAGUACUUGGAGUGGAUGGGUCAGGACACUGGAGACUUGAAUGCCAAAACCAAGAGAGGGGGGACAGACUCCCGUGUGUAUGCCACCCAGCACGCCCCACAGACCUGCCCUGUCCAGGACUAUAAGGAGUAUGCCCAGCGGCGGCCUCCCGCCAUGCGCUACGAGGAUGCCCCUUUCUACUUAUCCAUCAAGCCAGUCGUGAACCUGGCGGCUCUGCAUUGGUACAACUGCCAGGCCCUUGGCAAGAACAAGCUGGCCAAGAUGGUGAAGACCAUGUGUGAGAAGGGCAACAUCCCUGGCAGGAAAACCAACUUCAGUGUGUAUCAGAGCUGCAGCACCUUGUCUGAGGCCCAGAGCAACCAGCUCGUGCUGAUCUGUAACAAUCUGAGCCAGCAGGCUGCCCAGUCAGUGGCCGGCCACUCCAACAAUGGCAAUUUCAUCGUCUCCGCCUCCUAUGACUCUUCCUCAGACACCGCUUGACCAGGUGGCUUGAGCAAGACUCCAGUUUGGUUACUGUGUCCGGAGAAACUGUGAUUAUACACCGCUUCUCGUUCCCCUUCCUGUGCCCUCAGUGUUAAUUCACUUUAUAAAAAUAUAAAUAUAUAAUAUAUUUUUCUUUUUACAAAUAAGCCAAUGGAGAUAAUUUAGUAUUACUAACAUAGUAUUUAUAGGCUUAAGACAAAUGUACUUGUGGGCGAUCAAAUGUAAUUACUGUUACAGACUUUACAAAACCAUACGUGGUUCUCAGGCAACACAAAGUAGAGAGGGAAUUCUGUUUUUUAAAAACUGUCAAAAAGGAAAUUGAGAGUCAUCCUAGACUUAACAUGCUUGCGUCCUCAACUCCUGCUUUUCGUUCCCACCCCAACUCCCCUUUUUUGUCUCCUUAAUAAAUGGCUUUAUUUUUUUAAUUUUUAAAAUUCUAUAUUAAUCAAGAGGAGACAUUAACUUUACUGCUGACGCAAAACUGUAUUCAGCUAGAUCCACAAUAUGAAAAUGUAUAAGCUCAACAUCAAAUUAUUUACAUCUUCUCUUUUUUAACUUAAUUAGAGUUUUAGCUCCUGUGCCUCAUUUUUUACAAUGUAUGAGAAUCUAGAUGUUUAGCUAACAUCUUUUCUUUUUGGGGGGAAAGGGUAGAAGGAGGGAAUAAAGGUGCCAUUCUUUUUGGGAGAUACAUGAUUUUAAAAUAAUACCCAAAGUCUAAUAUUUUGGCUAAAAAGACUGUUACAUAGCUCAUUUUAACUAUUGUGCUUGAACCUGGAAAGAAUGUUUCUUUUUUUGUCCCUAAGAAAUGGGUAUAAAUGAAGUUUGACAGGAAAUUUAAAGCUACCAAAGCUUUGAAAAUGUUGCCAAGCAUUAGAUUGCCUAUAAAGAAGGUAAAAGGUGGAAAGUCUUACUAAAAAUCUAGAAGCAGUAGUCGAGACAACAAAAAAACUCAUCCUCUUCAAAGUUCAUAUUCCCUGAAUUAUUUACUUAGAAGCAUUAAACAGUCUCUUUUCUCCUGAGGCAAGGGUGUGUAUUCGACUCUGUGAUUGAGAUCCAAGGAAUAUUGGCACUCAUUUUAGGUAACAAUAUUUUGUUACCAGAUUUUGCUGAAUUCAAAGCAUUCUUGAAAAUGUGCGAGAUUUUUCUAUAGUAAAUAUAAAUGCGUUUAUCUGUGAUAUCCUGCAAUUAUUAUAAUAAUUUUGGUUAAACAUUUGUGGCAGUUUUUCCAAGGUCUUUGUUUUCAAGUCUUGAUGCCUGUGGUGAAUUAUUAGUUAAGAUAUUUCAAAAAUAAAAUAAAUUUAGACUUUAGAGCCACAAUAAAGCUGAGCUAGGUUCCUAUUCUGUAUAAUCAGCAACACACAGAAACUCCAAAUCUUGAUUGUUUUGUUGGACCCGUGAAUUCUAUUGGGAAAUAUUUGUUCUUCAAGGCAACCUCAUAAUUCACAUUAGCUAGAAAGGUAGGUGGUAUUUUGUACAUUAAUUUAGUGUAUAACCAGGACAAAUUUCAUUCUGAAUUGCUUUGCUAAAUCAUCACAGAGCUGAGCUCUCCCAUGGUCAGGGAACUCCUUCCAACACCAAGUCAUAAGCACAUAAAGACCCGUUCCUCUAAGCUGUGACCUUUCAUCUGGCUAAGGAGUGGGAAGUCAGCCAUGGACUUUGUGUCGUGGAGUUAACCUCAUGUUCAUGACUUUUCCUCCAUAGAGAAAUAUUCAUUUAUACAUCCAGAAACAAGAAGAAAGGGCAGAGAAUGUCUUGCUUUAUGUUUUUGUAUUGAUAGUGAUGAGAGCUGCCAUUUUUGAGCCAGCAUGCAUGCCAGCACUGUGCUAAGUGACUUACAUGGAUCACAUAUGUAAGUCAUAGUUACUAAUCUUAAAAAAAAAGAAAAAAAAAAUAGGAAAACACAGAUAAGGAUAAAGAAAACAAAAUACGUACUCGUAAGUCUUCUAGCCAAAGAUAACUACUGUUAACAUUUUGGCAAAUAUUUCUUCAGACAUAUUGCAGUACUUACAUAUUUAUUUCUAUAUAUAUUAAUAUUUUCAGCAACUUUGAAAAGGUGAGUUAUCUUUAUUUUAUGGUCAGGUCAAGAUAAGUCAAUUAGGUCAUAGCUAAAGAAAUGGUAGUCUGUCAUUUCAUUCCAGAGUUUUUUUCUAUUUAAGUUUCUCAGUACCAGCUCAUCAUUAAUUUCCAGUGGUUUGAUCCAGAGCUGGGGACACAGUGUCUUAACAUCUCUGAAGGAUGUCUGAUCAAAAGGAAUGCUGAGUAAUCUUCCAUGGUGGCAGCAUGUCCUCUAGUCCUCUCCCACACCCAUACAUUUGGAGCCACAGAGCCUCUUUCUCCCAGUUCUCUUUACAAAACCUUCCUGUUCGCCUUAUUCUAUAGUUAGUCCUUACGGCAUCAGACAGCCUACUUUAAGGGAACUCUUAAACUCUAAUGUUUAAAAAAAGGUCUCUGUAAAACACUUAAAAUGUUAUGGUGCAUUUAAUUUUUAAUUGACGUAGUUUCUAAAUUUUUGAUAUGUUUCUGACAGCACAGUAAGUUUGUCUUAAGGAAGAAGAGUAGUCAGUAUGCACUGUGAAAGCAGAACUAGAAAAUGUCAGUUCCCUAUCUGUGUUUAUUAAGGUACUAAAAUGAAAAUCUUUGUCCUGCUUAAUCAUAUUGCAUCUUCAUUUAGAAAAACACAAAUUGGGAAUGUGAAUUAUUUUUAUUUAUUUAUAUUUUUCUGUGAUAACUCAAGCCAAAUAGGAGCAUUGUGACUUUUAGUUUCAGAAAACUGUUUUCUGAAUGAUGGCUUGGUAGAAGCCUAGCCAAAUUACAGUAUCAGUCUUUGUUUGUUUGUUUGUUUGAACAGAGACAGGGUCUUGCUCUGUCACCCAGGCUGGAGUGCAGAGGUGCAGUCAUAGCUCACUGUCAACCUCAAACUCCAGGGCUCAAGAGAUCCUCCCACCUCAGCCUCCCAAAUAGCUGGAACUACAAGUGCACACCAUCACACUUGGCUAAUUUUUUGUAGAGAUGGGGUCUCACUGUGUUGCCCAGGCUGGUCUCGAACUCCUAGCCUCAAGAGAUCCUCCUGCCUUGGCCUCCCAAAGUGCUGGCGUUAUCUCUUGGAGUUACUUACAUUAUGAAAAAUCUACAACUACCUCUAAAUUUUAUUUUUAUCUAAAUGAUACUGAGAAGAUAGCACUGCCAGAUGCCAUUUUUAUUAUUUGGAAUAUUAACUUAAGAAAAAAUCAUGUUCAUGCUGUGGCAGAGGCAGAUGUCAAAAUUGCAUAUAUACUUUAGCAAAAAAUCAACAGUCCAGGAGAUGUUCACUACAACUGAAUGCGCUGCCUUUUCAGGCAAUCCUGUGGCUCAAAUAAAGCCAUAUUUGCAGUGCUUACACUUUAAGAUCAAUGUAAUGUCAUGUAAGAAACCCUCCAGUGUUCCUCACAUGACUGAAAGUUUUGCACUGUCUACAACAAAAACACUGAACACUGUCAGCAUUUGGAUGACAUAGCUGCAUAAUUUGGUCUUUCUACCAUAUUCAUGUGAGUGACUCUUGAAAACCAUAGAUGCUAGCUAUUUUUAAAAAAACUAUAAUGUUUGAAAAAGUUAAGAGAUAGGAUAUUUAUUCAAGACAGCUUAUUCUAGAUUCCAUUUGAUAUCAUGGUUAUUAGGGCUGGUCUGAAUAUGACUUAUAAAUAUAUAUCAGCAAUUUAGGAUAUUUAUAAUUAUUUUUCCCUAUGGUUAAAUUUUCCCUAUGUUAAAUCACUGCCUGUUCUACAAAAGAGUAGUCUGAAAAUCUUCUGGCAUACAUUUGAUCUCUUUGGUUUUUCAGUUAGAUUAUUAUUAGCUGAAACUUUCAUAGCAUUUACUUGACUAAAUCAUAUGGCUUAGCUUGCAGAUGCCAUGAAAUCAAUGACUUUAUUGAGAUGAGAAUUUGUAGUCACAUCAACAGUAUUUAUUGAACAGCUAGGGGCCAAACCUGGAGGGGUAUAAAGACACAUGAAAUAGUCCCUGCUCUCAAAGAAUUUAUAAAAGACAUUGUAAUAAAAGUUAGUUCAUUUUUGAGAGCCCAGCAAAAAACUCUAUGCUAAUACUAUUUUGCAUAGUUUUCCAAACUUUGUACCCAUGCAAUUUAUCCAUUAUUUAUUCAUUGAAUAUGUUGGUCUGCUGUGGAAUACGUAAUUCUGCUUUGAGUAUUUUCUGGAGAAUCUUUCUUAGAGCCUGUUUUAAAAUCAAUAAAGUGAAGGCAUUUCUGUACCAUCCACUGUGUUCAUGUAGGUGCACAUAUGCAUCAGAGUGUACAGAUCUGUCAUCAAUGACUAUCACCUCUUGAGCACUGACAAUGUGCCAUUGUACUGAGUGCUUUAUAAGUUGUUUCACUUAAUUCUCACAAUAGUCCCAUUAGGUAAGUAUUAUUAUUUCCCUUUUAUAAUUGAGGAAAUCCAGAAAAGUCAAAUGGCUUGCCCAUGUCACAGUUAAUAUGUAAGAGCAUCCGUAUCUGAAAUUAGAUCCAGAUCCCAUUAAGCACUCUCUUUUUCUGCUGUAGCUACUUGUUCAAGAAGUGAUUUGCUGUGCUUCUGUAGACCCUCUGAAGUUAUAAAUUAUAAAUGAAAUCCCAGGUGUACUAAAAUCAUCAAAUUAAUUCAACUCAUUGAUUGAGAUCAAUGUUAGCACAACAUUAUUUAGGCGUCAUUACUGUAGUAUUUUGAGAUGAGAUAUUAAGCAGUUUGUUUAUCCCUGGUUACCAGCAGAGAGCAGAAGUUUGUGUCACUCUAAAAAACACCUAACUUUGUCAUGGAGGCAAGUGUGUAUAUGUGUAUAAUUUAUUUUUACCCCAAUUAAAGCCAAAACCCCAAUUUCAAGAGAGUCCUUUAUAAUUCAGGCAGGGAAGUGGGAGGGUCUAGGCAGAGGGACUGCCUAUAAGCCAGUAUCGAUUGCCAUUGACCAGAUACUAAAUAUGAAUUAGAGGUAGACUGUGAACCUAUUCAGAUUUUUUCUGGUUCGACUAUCUGCAGUUUAAUGUGAGACAGACACUUCUGAUCUUAAUCAGCCCUCUUCUGACUGAUUUUCUUUAUCUAUAGGAAAGGUAUAUUUUGAUCCUUAUUUCUCUAGCCAAAAUAAAGCUGUAAUACUAAGCACCUGUAAAUAAAAACUCUCUCCCAGAUGACAGAAGAAAUAGAUACCUAAGCCUAGGGAGGAAAGUCAAGGGGAAUGUAUAAUUUCUUGGAGCAAGAUAUCUUUUAAAGCGUUCAUUAAAAAAUAGUUACAAGUACUGAAAGAAUUAGCAAGUUCUCUAUCAGCUUAAUAAAUGUUUCCCAAAUAGAAUUCUAUUAUACAAGAUAUGUCUCUGUACAUCUACCAUACAAUAUGGUACAGAUAGGCAGUGAUCAAUUAAGAAAUGCACAUUGGCAAGGGCAUCCUCAAUCGUUGUUUAGUGCAUGGUAUUCAAACAUUGCUUUCCCUUCCCACUUGGAUCUGGUUAACAUGAUAUUGAGUGCAUAGCCUUUCAUAAAGCAAAGUGAUGAAGCUAGGAUAAUUUUAGAGAUCCUUGCCAUCAAAUAGAACUGGAAUAAAGAAAUACAUUGCAGAUAUCAUUCUUUUGGGAGUUGGUGUAUUUCUAGUGAUAUAACAACAGAAAAGAAGAGAUGAUAUUGAUGGAGUACCAAGAACUCUAAUUUUACUUUUCUAAACAGAAAAGGAAGACAUUUAAAAUUCCUCAUGGUCCAGCCUGUUUGUAAAUUGACCAGUUGGGCCUGCCAAAGCUGAGCAAAAGCUUGAAAAAUUUUUUUUAAUGGCAUUUUAAUACACUUACGUUGAGUUCUUAUGUAAACAAUGACUUUUGUGAAUUAGAACCAGAGUAUUAAUUAGGUCAGAGUCCCAGUUUGAUUAGAAUAUUAAUUAGGUCUGUGUGUUAAUGUAAACCAUUGUCUUUGUUGUAUUAUUAGUCAUAGAGGCUAGAUCUGGAAAGGACCCAAGAGAUCAUCUAGCCCAGUGAUUUUCAAUGCUGUGAAGAGUAGGAGUCACCACGUCCUCAUGUAGGUAGGGAGUGGGGAGCGCAAGAAGAUAGAAAUAGCCAAGAGAACACAACCUCAAACAAAUUCCCCAGAGGUCUCAUGUUUCCUACCCCCUCCCCUCCUUUGAGACUCACUAGACUGACUGAGCUGCUGUUCCCUCUGGAAUGCAUCCUUCAGGUGUGCUAGCUGGAAAAUAAAAUUGGAAACAUUUAAUCUACCUUUUAAUGUAUUUAUUUGUUUUUCGAGACAGGGUCUCGCUCUGUUGUCCAGGCUGGAGUGCAGUGGCACAAUCAAGACUCACUGCAGUGGCACUGCAGCCUUGAACUCCUGGGCUCAAGCAAUCCUCCCAACUCAACCUCCCAAGUAGCUGGGACUCCCGGUUCAUACCAUCCUGCCUGACUAAUUUUUAAAAAUUUUUUGUAGACAUGGGAUCUCACUGUGUUGCCCAGGCUGGUCUCAAACUCCUGGACUCAAGUGAUCCCCCCACCUCAGCCUCCCAAAGUGCUAGAAUUACAGGCAUGAGCCACUGCUCUGUCCUCAUCCACCCUUUAACAAAAGAGGCAAUAGCCCCAGAGAAAGGAGGUGAAUGCCCAGGUGCUCACACCCUGUUAGGGUGUGAGCUUUCCCUUGUCAGGGUUAAAGCCGGGACUAGAGGCAGGCACCCUGACUUCCUGUCCACAGGUAGAGUUUAGAGAGGAAAAACAACCCUAUAUUUCUACUUCUUGUUUUCCAAAUUUUAAUUGUUUUUAAAACCCACAAAUUUCUCUUAGGAGUAGAUUCAAGCUGCCAAGUUCCAAUAGGCUGUUCUUGAAUGUGACAUUUCACUUUUCAUUGUGUUGUGUUACAUCUUAGUUUUAGCAACUUUUCUUUUUGGAGUUUGAUAGGAAAAUCUGUAAAUGUAAUUGUUCUUUGAUUCUAACAAACAUCUCUCAGCCUACCCAAUUUAUAUUUAGUUUUCAGUUAUGGAGGGGAAACUACAGUCUUCAAGAAUAUCAAUUCUAGUUAUAGAUUAUGAACAAAAAUACAUUUUUGUUUAAUUUGAUAUUCACUUGGAUAUCGAGCUACAUAGCAUCUAUACUACUGGUUCUGAAUGCAACCCACAGUAUUUUUUAGUCUGGCAAGUUUUACAAAUCGUAUUUAAAGUUUUGGGACAUAUCCUCAGUCAAAAGGAUCAAAUUUCUAUCAACAUAAUUAGGAAGUUUCUGAAGUAAAUUUAUUUAGAGAUAGUAAAGGGGAAAAAUGGUAACUAAGGAAAGAGGCCUACAGUAAGUAGAUGUAGAAAUUCAAACUUACUUAAAUGCAAAUUAUUUGUAUUUCUCAUCUUGCUUACUCUUCUGAAAAGGAACUCAAGCAUAAAUAUUUAAACGUUUCACAAAUUUUUAUUUUACAAAUCAUAUUUACCAGAUCAUAGUUGAAAAAGUUCAAAUUUUAGAUGUUUUUUAAAAAGGUACAGUGUGAUUUGUCUUUUUUUUGUAAUGUUGAAUUAUGUUAGACUUCUAAUGUUUGUCUUGAUAUUACACUGGAAUUAGACAGCAUUUUUACCAUUUAUACAUUCAUUUCAAUAAGAGCUUUGAAAAUGCUUUGGCAUUGUUUGUUUGUGAUAAGUAGAAUUAGGAAGAUAUCAGCAAUAUAGAUUCCUAACAGUAAUUGUGUAUACUGUGUUUUAGUGAUUUUUAUGUCCAUUUAUUUUCUGUAAUUCUUUUAUAAAUCCCUUAGUGUACUUCCACUAGAAAUUAAUUUAUAAUUGUUUAUUUAUAUUGGAUGAAGUAGGAGGUCCAUGUUUAGUAUUAACCCACUCAGAUUAACUUUAUCUAACUGAACUUUUAUAUCUAUAACCCAUUAGAUUGUUACAACUUUUUAAACAGCAUUUAUAAUGAAAUAACUUUUGUUUUAUAAAGCAUUUGUUACAAAAAAAAAAAAACACCUUGCCAAAAAUCAUUACGAUUUCUAUGCAUUGUGUAAUAUUCAGUGAUGUUGAGAUUUUGCAUGUUGUUACAGGUGCUCUUUCAUAUGUGUGUUUGUGGUGUUGAUGUGGAAUUGUUAACCACUGCUGCUAUCACUUAUUGUAGUUAAACUGAAAAACUGUGUUAAAAGGCUGUGCCAGUCAACAUUUCUAUGUGUGACUUAAGUAACUGUGUACUUCAUUGUUUAAUAUUUUGAGCCAGCACUUAGUGGCCUCUACAGAAGGAAAUAUUGUAGUUGUCAAAGUGGUGCCAAACUUGAAAAUCUUGUGUCAUGUUUAUAAUUCCAGGCCAGGUCAGCUUUUCUUCAACACUUUCCGAGCUCUUUGAAAGCAAAAAACAUUUGCAAAAAGAGAAAGAAAGCAAGAAUUCUGAACUUUUCUAAUACUCUCUCCUCUAGAAUUUUAAAUAUUUUUUUCUUUUGAUGUUUGAGUAUCUUACAGAAAAAUCCAAUCAAAUGACUAGCGGUAGAAUUUCCCUUGAUCUGGAUAUUUUUAGGCUGAACAGUGUAAUAGCAGAGGACUAUGAGGUGCAUACAUUAUUUUUGUUGGCUAUCAUGGCUUAUUGUUUGAAUUUCAUUUAAUAACAAUAUUCAGGCUGGAGGUGGUGACUCACACCUGCAUUCCCAGCACUUUGGGAGACUGAGGCGGGCGGAUCACCUGAGAUCAGGAGUUCGAGGCCAGCCUGGCCAACAUGACGAAGCCCAGUCUCUACUAAAAAUACAAAAAUUAGCUGGGUGUGGUGGCUCACACCUGUAAUCCCAGCUACUUGGGAGGCUGAGGCAGGAGCAUUGCUUGAGCCUGGGAGGUGGAGGUUGUAGUGAUCUGAGAUCACACUACUGCACUCCAGCCUGGGUGAGGGAGCAAGGCUCCAACCCCCCUAAAAAGAAAAAAAGAAUAUUCAGUAAUUUUAUUUCCUUUAUUAAGAACCAUUGAAACCUCACAGUUCCCACUUGUUAACUUUUACAUUCAGCAUGUACACAGACUUACUUAACAUACUUGGUUGCCUUAUGGCCAUCAGGAUUUUUUCAUGCCCACCUGUCUAGUUUGGUACCUGGUGUUUCCAUCUUGCCUCAGCAAUUCCAAACAAACUGAAAGUAAAGAGAAAAUCGUUUCAACAUAUUGACUCUACUACACAUUGUUAAAAUUUAAUAUGGGAGGAAUACCACUAUACUUUUAUUUAUACUCUUAAAAUGAGUGGGGGGAAGCUGUCAUAAAGUGUUAAGAAAAGAAGGCUGCUUCCUGAAGAGCCUUUUUACACCAACAUGCCAGAUCUCCACACUUGAUGCAGGGUUUCCUUCUGUCAGUUCAAUGGGCUUGUAAUUACAAGAUUCUUUUAAUAAAGGGGUAAUCUCCUGAACUUUAUAGAAACUUGUUGUGUGACUGUCACAUAUGCAGCAACAGCCAAUGCUGUAUUUGGACACAUUGCUGAUGAAAUUACUGAUUUAAUUCUAAGACUAUCAAAACUAAUUCGUCAAGGUCCCCACCACCUCUUUGCUUAAAGGAAAACAAAGGCAGAUUUUAACUGUGAGCCUCUUCUCUAGAAUAUGCUGUAGACAUUUGCCCCUCCGUGAGGUGAUAAAGCAAUAAAAAUAAAUUUAAUUAUGUGUGGUCUAAAGAAGUUCUACCUCUGUCCAUUGGCCUCCAGAGUCACACAAAAUUAUUUCUUGAUUCCUACAUCAGAGGUUUUCAGGCAGAGCCUUUGUACCAAGAAUUCCUUUUAUAUUUUGGACACCAAAGAUUAUGGCAUGAUAUAUCCUGAUGAUUAACAAUUUAGCAGUGGGCACAUUUAUUUGAGUCCUGCUCUUGGAUUUAUUUCCCACCUUUGGGUCUUACGUACAUUUUGUAUUUCUGUCCUGAGGACUUUUUGCCUCAGGCAGUUUUUAAAUCAAAAAAAUAUAUAUAUAUUUAUUAGGUUUCUAAUUUAUAGAGUUUCCAAUUUCUCCCACAAUUUUAAAUGUUUUCACUGCCAAAGUUAGCAGUAGAUUUGCUAGGUUAAUGCCAUGGUCAGUAAUAGUUUGUACCUUUUAUGUUGUAGCCUGAAAAUGUAACUCUAACCCCGUAGGCCUGAAACCUGGUGGGAAGAUGAUUGAAAGUGUUUUAGAUUCAACAGAUUGACUAUGUAUGACUUAUCUAUUAAAAUGAAGAACUUCCAUGGUUUAAUAGAAUGAAUGCUGUAUUCAACAAGGUCUUCCAUCCUUCUUAUAAAUCUUAAGACUGUGUUUAAGCUUUCUUUCACUUUUACUCUAUCCCUUGGAAGUUAAUUGGGAAUAAAAAGAUUUAUCAAUUUAGUCACUAUAAUUUAAGGCCAGGCAUCUGCUUGGAAAUACAAUAACCACAAUUAAUACUUAGAGAAAAUUGUUUCAACAGAUUAACUCUGCUAUUUUAAAAACUAUAGUAGUGUUCUUUGAGGAUGCAUUUACUUUUCCCCAAAUUUGAUAGAUAGUUAUUUUUAUAUAUUUUUUCUGGCCACUUGGCUUCUAACUGAUUAACAUGAAAAACGCACGUGUGCCUGUUUCACUCAAAUCAUAUUUUACAACUUUUUAAAAGCUGCUACAGUUAUAGUUUGUGAAAGAGGAGAAAGGUGAAUUGCAACAGAGGGAAAUUACUGUUACUGUGUCAAAUAUGUGACUGAUGCUUUUGGUCAGAUAAUCUGCUGCCUGUCAAUAUUUGUAAUAACAGAAUUUUUUGUUAAGAGUACUCUCAUCUUUAUUUUGCUGCUCACUGAUUUUUUACACUAAGAUGUUCUCAUCUUUGUCGACUCACUGUUUUUGCUUCAUAUUUGUCUGUGUACUUGUGCUCUAAAUAAAAAUCUAGUUUUAUGUCUAGUUUAUUCCAUUGUGUGUAUAAUGUUUGCCUCUGAUGUAGUGUAAUUUUCUAUUGUUUUUGAUGUUUGUUGGUACAGCCUAAAACUUAUGGAAAUAAGAAAAGCAAUCCAAUAAAGUCAGCUAAUGAGUGUCAA